AGUUCCGUCGCAGCCGGGAUUUGGGUCGCAGUUCUUGUUUGUGGAUCGCUGUGAUCGUCACUUGACAAUGCAGAUCUUCGUGAAGACUCUGACUGGUAAGACCAUCACCCUCGAGGUUGAGCCCAGUGACACCAUCGAGAAUGUCAAGGCAAAGAUCCAAGAUAAGGAAGGCAUCCCUCCUGACCAGCAGAGGCUGAUCUUUGCUGGAAAACAGCUGGAAGAUGGGCGCACCCUGUCUGACUACAACAUCCAGAAAGAGUCCACCCUGCACCUGGUGCUCCGUCUCAGAGGUGGGAUGCAAAUCUUCGUGAAGACACUCACUGGCAAGACCAUCACCCUUGAGGUCGAGCCCAGUGACACCAUCGAGAACGUCAAAGCAAAGAUCCAGGACAAGGAAGGCAUUCCUCCUGACCAGCAGAGGUUGAUCUUUGCCGGAAAGCAGCUGGAAGAUGGGCGCACCCUGUCUGACUACAACAUCCAGAAAGAGUCUACCCUGCACCUGGUGCUCCGUCUCAGAGGUGGGAUGCAGAUCUUCGUGAAGACCCUGACUGGUAAGACCAUCACCCUCGAGGUGGAGCCCAGUGACACCAUCGAGAAUGUCAAGGCAAAGAUCCAAGAUAAGGAAGGCAUUCCUCCUGAUCAGCAGAGGUUGAUCUUUGCCGGAAAACAGCUGGAAGAUGGUCGUACCCUGUCUGACUACAACAUCCAGAAAGAGUCCACCUUGCACCUGGUACUCCGUCUCAGAGGUGGGAUGCAAAUCUUCGUGAAGACACUCACUGGCAAGACCAUCACCCUUGAGGUCGAGCCCAGUGACACUAUCGAGAACGUCAAAGCAAAGAUCCAAGACAAGGAAGGCAUUCCUCCUGACCAGCAGAGGUUGAUCUUUGCCGGAAAGCAGCUGGAAGAUGGGCGCACCCUGUCUGACUACAACAUCCAGAAAGAGUCUACCCUGCACCUGGUGCUCCGUCUCAGAGGUGGGAUGCAGAUCUUCGUGAAGACCCUGACUGGUAAGACCAUCACUCUCGAAGUGGAGCCGAGUGACACCAUUGAGAAUGUCAAGGCAAAGAUCCAAGACAAGGAAGGCAUCCCUCCUGACCAGCAGAGGUUGAUCUUUGCCGGAAAACAGCUGGAAGAUGGUCGUACCCUGUCUGACUACAACAUCCAGAAAGAGUCCACCUUGCACCUGGUGCUCCGUCUCAGAGGUGGGAUGCAGAUCUUCGUGAAGACCCUGACUGGUAAGACCAUCACUCUCGAGGUGGAGCCGAGUGACACCAUUGAGAAUGUCAAGGCAAAGAUCCAAGACAAGGAAGGCAUCCCUCCUGACCAGCAGAGGUUGAUCUUUGCUGGGAAACAGCUGGAAGAUGGACGCACCCUGUCUGACUACAACAUCCAGAAAGAGUCCACCCUGCACCUGGUGCUCCGUCUUAGAGGUGGGAUGCAGAUCUUCGUGAAGACCCUGACUGGUAAGACCAUCACUCUCGAAGUGGAGCCGAGUGACACCAUUGAGAAUGUCAAGGCAAAGAUCCAAGACAAGGAAGGCAUCCCUCCUGACCAGCAGAGGUUGAUCUUUGCUGGGAAACAGCUGGAAGAUGGACGCACCCUGUCUGACUACAACAUCCAGAAAGAGUCCACCCUGCACCUGGUGCUCCGUCUUAGAGGUGGGAUGCAGAUCUUCGUGAAGACCCUGACUGGUAAGACCAUCACUCUCGAAGUGGAGCCGAGUGACACCAUUGAGAAUGUCAAGGCAAAGAUCCAAGACAAGGAAGGCAUCCCUCCUGACCAGCAGAGGUUGAUCUUUGCUGGGAAACAGCUGGAAGAUGGACGCACCCUGUCUGACUACAACAUCCAGAAAGAGUCCACCCUGCACCUGGUGCUCCGUCUCAGAGGUGGGAUGCAAAUCUUCGUGAAGACCCUGACUGGUAAGACCAUCACCCUCGAGGUGGAGCCCAGUGACACCAUCGAGAAUGUCAAGGCAAAGAUCCAAGAUAAGGAAGGCAUCCCUCCUGAUCAGCAGAGGUUGAUCUUUGCUGGGAAACAGCUGGAAGAUGGACGCACCCUGUCUGACUACAACAUCCAGAAAGAGUCCACUCUGCACUUGGUCCUGCGCUUGAGGGGGGGUGUCUAAGUUUCCCCUUUUAAGGUUUCAACAAAUUUCAUUGCACUUUCCUUUCAAUAAAGUUGUUGCAUUCCCAA